GAAGCUUUUUAGCUUGAUGAAAUCCCAGUUGUCUGUUUUUGCUUUAGUUGCCUGUGCUUUUGAGGUCUUACGUAAAAACCCUGUGCCCAAAAAACCUGUGCCCAAGAUGAGUGUCCUGGAGCACUUCCCCAGUGUUUUCUUCUAGUAGUUUUAUAGGUUUUGGGACUGGAUUUCUGUCUACAGUCCUGGAGUUUUGCUGCCCUCACUUUGGUUUUUCACUCACUUCUCUGCAUGGCUUUCCAAUAGCAAUAGCUCCCAGAUAGCAAGCAUGGGUGGGUGGGGGGAGUAUUACAUGCGUCACUUCACUUAAUCCUCAUGGUCUGUCUACUUAUUUUCAGAUGAGAAAACAGGUUUAGAGAAGUUGUGAUCUACCUAAAGUCAUGCACAGUUUCACUCAAGUGUCUGACUCCAGAUCCGCUUGCCUCUAAUCUCUCAUAGUAACUUGUUGACACAUUUUCUCCAGUUGUCCUGUCUUGCUUAAAAAGCUGUGGGGAAGACUCAGCCUGGCUCAGGUAGUAUUAGACCAGCAGUCCCUGGUGUGGCAUACUCAGUUUUGGCAUUGCCUUCCUGGUAUGUUUUAAAGAAAACUCAUCAGAACCUUUGUAUCUUUUUUAUUUUCCUUGAGACAGGGUCUCGCUCUGUCACCCAGGCUGGAGUGCAGGCUCGAUCACGGCUCACUGCAGCCUCAACCUCCUGGACUCAAGUGAUCCUCCCACCUCAGCUUCCCAAGUAGCUGGGACUACAGGUGCACACCACCAUGCCCUGCUAAUUUUUUGUAUUUUCUGUAGAUACUGGAUUUCACCAUGGUGCCCAGGCUGGUCUUGAAUUCCUGGGCUCAAGCAAUCUACCUGCGUUGGCCUCCCAAAGUGCUGGGAUUACAGACAUGAACCACCACACCUGGCAGAACCUUUGUAUCUUGAAAGCUGUGUAAAUACAAUCAGUGUGGGUAUCUUAGUCCCUCCUUAUCAGCGGUAGUAGUUUCACUUACCAAUGGUCAGCUGCGAUCUGAAACUAUUAAGUGGAAAAUUCAUAAGAAAUAGUCAAUUCAUGGCUGGGCAUGGUGGCUCAGGCCUGUAAUCCUAGCAGUUUGGGAGGCUGAGGUGGACCUGAGGAUCACCUGAGGUCUGCAGUUUGAGACCAGGCUGGCCAAUACGGUGAAAACCCUGUCUCUACUAAAAAAAAUAUACAAAUUAGCCGGGCAUGGUGGUGUGCGCCUGUAAUCCCAACUACUUGGAAGGCUGAAGCAGGAGAAUUGCUUGAACCCAGGAGGUGGAGGUUGCAAUGAGCCAAAAUUGUGCCACUGCACUCCAGCCUGGGUGACUGAGACUCCGUUUCAAAAAAAAAAAAAAAAAGAAAUAAUCAGUUCAUAAGUCUUAAAUUACAUGGUUUUGCAGUGCUUGUGUUCAUGUCACCCUUAUAUUUAAUAAUGGCCCCAAAGCAAAAGAUGCUGGCAAUUUGGAUAUUGUAAAGAGAAGCUGUAAAGUGUUUCCUUUUACUGAAAAGGUGAAAGAUCUCAAUUUAAUAUGGAAAUAAAAAAAUUUGUAUGCUGAGGCUGCUAACGUCUAUGGUCGUGAUGUCUCGGGAGUCGGAUGUUGAGGCUCAGCAGUCUCAUGGCAGCAGUGCCUGUUCACAGCCCCAUGGCAGCGUUACCCAGUCCCAAGGCUCCUCCUCACAGUCCCAGGGCAUAUCCAGCUCCUCUACCAGCACGAUGCCAAACUCCAGCCAGUCCUCUCACUCCAGCUCUGGGACACUGAGCUCCUUAGAGACAGUGUCCACUCAGGAACUCUAUUCUAUUCCUGAGGACCAAGAACCUGAGGACCAAGAACCUGAGGAGCCUACCCCUGCCCCCUGGGCUCGAUUAUGGGCCCUUCAGGAUGGAUUUGCCAAUCUUGAGACAGAGUCUGGCCAUGUUACCCAAUCUGAUCUUGAACUCCUGCUGUCAUCUGAUCCUCCUGCCUCAGCCUCCCAAAGUGCUGGGAUAAGAGGUGUGAGGCACCAUCCCCGGCCAGUUUGCAGUCUAAAAUGUGUGAAUGACAACUACUGGUUUGGGAGGGACAAAAGCUGUGAAUAUUGCUUUGAUGAACCACUGCUGAAAAGAACAGAUAAAUACCGAACAUACAGCAAGAAACACUUUCGGAUUUUCAGGGAAGUGGGUCCUAAAAACUCUUACAUUGCAUACAUAGAAGAUCACAGUGGCAAUGGAACCUUUGUAAAUACAGAGCUUGUAGGGAAAGGAAAACGCCGUCCUUUGAAUAACAAUUCUGAAAUUGCACUGUCACUAAGCAGAAAUAAAGUUUUUGUCUUUUUUGAUCUGACUGUAGAUGAUCAGUCAGUUUAUCCUAAGGCAUUAAGAGAUGAAUACAUCAUGUCAAAAACUCUUGGAAGUGGUGCCUGUGGAGAGGUAAAGCUGGCUUUCGAGAGGAAAACAUGUAAGAAAGUAGCCAUAAAGAUCAUCAGCAAAAGGAAGUUUGCUAUUGGUUCAGCAAGAGAGGCAGACCCAGCUCUCAAUGUUGAAACAGAAAUAGAAAUUUUGAAAAAGCUAAAUCAUCCUUGCAUCAUCAAGAUUAAAAACUUUUUUGAUGCAGAAGAUUAUUAUAUUGUUUUGGAAUUGAUGGAAGGGGGAGAGCUGUUUGACAAAGUGGUGGGGAAUAAACGCCUGAAAGAAGCUACCUGCAAGCUCUAUUUUUACCAGAUGCUCUUGGCUGUGCAGUACCUUCAUGAAAACGGUAUUAUACACCGUGACUUAAAGCCAGAGAAUGUUUUACUGUCAUCUCAAGAAGAGGACUGUCUUAUAAAGAUUACUGAUUUUGGGCACUCCAAGAUUUUGGGAGAGACCUCUCUCAUGAGAACCUUAUGUGGAACCCCCACCUACUUGGCGCCUGAAGUUCUUGUUUCUGUUGGGACUGCUGGGUAUAACCGUGCUGUGGACUGCUGGAGUUUAGGAGUUAUUCUUUUUAUCUGCCUUAGUGGGUAUCCACCUUUCUCUGAGCAUAGGACUCAAGUGUCACUGAAGGAUCAGAUCACCAGUGGAAAAUACAACUUCAUUCCUGAAGUCUGGGCAGAAGUCUCAGAGAAAGCUCUGGACCUUGUCAAGAAGUUGUUGGUAGUGGAUCCAAAGGCACGUUUUACGACAGAAGAAGCCUUAAGACACCCGUGGCUUCAGGAUGAAGACAUGAAGAGAAAGUUUCAAGAUCUUCUGUCUGAGGAAAAUGAAUCCACAGCUCUACCCCAGGUUCUAGCCCAGCCUUCUACUAGUCGAAAGCGGCCCCGUGAAGGGGAAGCCGAGGGUGCCGAGACCACAAAGCGCCCAGCUGUGUGUGCUGCUGUGUUGUGAACUCCGUGGUUUGAACACGAAAGAAAUGUACCUUCUUUCACUCUGUCAUCUUUCUUUUCUUUGAGUCUGUUUUUUUAUAGUUUGUAUUUUAAUUAUGGGAAUAAUUGCUUUUUCACAGUCACUGAUGUACAAUUAAAAACCUGAUGGAACCUGG